AAGCCGCGCGUCCAGUUGCUUGGAGAAGCCCGUUCACCGCCUCCAGCUGCUGCUCUCCUCGACAUGGACCCUGAGACCUGCCCCUGCCCUUCUGGUGGCUCCUGCACCUGCGCGGACUCCUGCAAGUGCGAGGGAUGCAAAUGCACCUCCUGCAAGAAGAGCUGCUGCUCCUGCUGCCCUGCGGAGUGUGAGAAGUGUGCCAAGGACUGUGUGUGCAAAGGCGGAGAGGCAGCUGAGGCAGAAGCAGAGAAGUGCAGCUGCUGCCAGUGAGAAGGCACCCCUCCGUGUGGAGCACGUGGAGAUAGUGCCAGGUGGCUCAGUGCCACCUAUGCCUGUGGUGAAGUGUGGCUGGUGUCCCCUUCCCCUGCUGACCUUGGAGGAAUGACAAUAAAUCCCAUGAACAGCA